CCUCAACAGAGAAUUCUUUAUUAUGUCCAAAAGAGCACAACAAAAACAUCCCAACAAUACAUAAACCUAUAUAUAAAAUAUAGAAUAUCUCCAAAUUUUUACUUUCUAUGGCAGCACGCCAAUAUAUACAAGAGAACAUAUUGAUGGGGCAAAGGGAAAACUGAUUUGGGCAAUGACUUAAUUAGUCAGGCAUUAACAUUCAGAGACCUGGUAAACAGCAACUUUAGUCAGAAAAGCAAUAUGAGAAGAGUUCCUGUGAAGCUGGGAUUUACAUACUUCAUUCUCCGUUCCUGGUCAUUUCAUCCACAACUUGACUGUUGUCAAUCAUGGUUCUUUGCCUUUGGAGUGGUACUAUGAAGGUACAGAGAAUAGAGAAUGCCCAUCUCAGUACCAAAAUUUCACCAUGAAAAAUCAUAAUAGAAAUAACAAAGCUUAAAAAAAUGCUGCAUUUCAGAAGUAUUUACCCUAAUAAUUUUUAAGAAAGCUUACCAUAAAUACUUCUAGGUUAGUGACAAAAUUUGAGUUUGGGAAAAAUAUACAUAUCAGGGAUGCAAGCUUAUUCUGUGCAGUUUACACCUGCAUAGGCCACCCAUCUCGGCCUCCCUAAGUGCUGGGAUUACAGGCGUGAGCCACCACGCCUGGCCCUGGUAUAUGUUUUAAGUCAACCAGUUCUCCUUAAGUACUUGUUUCAACAUCAUGUUAUUGUGUACUACAGAAGCAAUCUCUCAGUUAUGAAAAAUAAAAUCAGUUUCAGGGCUCACAAAGUAAAAAGGGAAAUUCUUUCCCAAUCUCCCCUUCCCCCACCACCUGGCUUUUUUUGUUUAAAAAAUUAAAUUCAAAUGUAUAAGACCAAGCACCGGCACUUUCCAAAAAACAAAAAUGAAGCCAAAUCACAAAAUUACUCAAUAGUUAUAGAAGACAGCUCUGAUUUUGGGGGGUCAUCUCUGGUUGCCUCAGUACAAGCAUUGAUCUUUGGCUGCUAGCCUUGCUUUUUAGUUUAAGGAAUAUGGAUCCUAUUAUUGGUAUUAAAAAUUAUACUUCUAAAACUAUUGAAGGCUAUUACUAAUUAUUUCAGUUCUCUAUAUAGUAUUCGUACCUCAGUUUAAUAGUGCUUACUAAGUCAUUUAAAUAAUAGGUCUCUGUUGAAAAAUAUUAGAAUUGUACCCUUCCACCUCUAAAAAGUCAGAGUUCAGGAUGAAAAGGUAUGAAGUCCUCUGUUGGUCAUAGUAUUUUGUGGGCUAAAUCAUUGUCUAAAAUCAGAAAGACAGCGCAGUGGAAGGUUCUAGGAGUUGCAUGGAUCUGGGUUAGAAUCUCAGUGCCUCUCGCAACCAAUUGUUUAAAAUGUGGGCAGAUUAGUCCCUCCAUUUCCAUUUUCUCUUUUGUGAAAUAAUUAUUAUUUUGCAAGGCUCAUGUGACAAAGUGGAUUAGUAUGUGUGUCUAGCAUAAUGUAGAUGCUAAAAUUAAAUGAUUGACUUGGCACCAGUCAGAGUUUAUUCACUUUUAAUAUUGAUUUUGAAAGUCUCCAGUCAGAUUGCUUAAUUGAUACACAUUAAUUUUUACUGUUAGAUUUUUAACUUAUUAUUAAACACCAAGUUUGAUAAUAAAUACUAUUAGUGAGGUAGGAGGUGGAACUUGACUCCAGACCAGAUUGAAGACUGGCUGAAACAGGGAAGAGGUGAAAGCACCUCUCCAUAAGACACGCCCACCAGUGCCAUGUCAGUUUACCAUUGCCAUGGUAACACCUGGAAAUUACCACCCCUUUCCAUGGCAACAACCUGGAAGUUACCACCCUUUUUCUAGAGGUUUCUGAUUAACCUGCCCUCUUAAUUUGCAUGUAAUUAAAAAUGGGCAUAAAUAUGACUGCAGAACUGCCCUUGAGCUGCUGUUAUGGAGCAGUCACAGAGCUUAACACUGCCACGUCAGUAAAGCAGUUUCCUUCUACCGCAGGGUCGCUCUUCAGCUCUUUCCUAAGUGCAGUUGAGAAUCUUCCUGGGCUGAGCCCCAGUUUGGGAGCUUGCCUGCCCUUCAUCAAUAGCAGUAGUAAUAGUAAUGAUGAUGGUAGCCAGCCAGAUAUAGUGAAGUGUUCUAUGUGUUCUCAGUUACUCUGAACAAGGGCCCUCAAAGGGCAGGUAUUUUUAUGUUCUUUUUGCUGACAAGAAACUGAGGCUUAGUGAGACUGAGAUUUAGAAAGUAAUGAAAGGAAAAAGUUAUGUUAAAUGAUCACUUUUUUAUGGAGCCAUGCUUUUUUGUGCUUAAUUUAUUGCCUAUUGCUCAUAUGUGUUUUACAUUGUUCAGUGUUUUCUCAAGAUAAGCAAUGAGAAGUAACAGCUGUAGUCAACUUUCUUCCCCAAGUACUAAGUAAAUAAGGUGGUUAGGUGUAGAAUGGAAUUAGCUAUGGAAUGCUGAUUGUUUAUUUUCUAUGUAGGAUGAAAGAAAUUAGGCAUGAAGAAGGAAGAUAAUUUUCUACUUGCUAUAGAUUUGAAAUAGUUUUCUUUCUUUUGCUUUUUUUUUGUUUGACCUACUGAGGAGUUCAGAGUGGUUAACUGAAACAGACUCUAAAAAUACCCUUUGGUAGCGUGCUCACUGAAGUAUUUUCUGUUUGUCUAAAAUUAGCAGAUUUGAGCAGAUUUGAGCAGUGUACUCUGGUUUUCCAAAGCCUUCCAUUAGGUGACUUCUUAUUCUGGUGUACUUUGUUAUCUUUCUGGAUAACACGUUUGAUGGGUGUUAAAAGGUAAAGCCAGGAAUGGCUUUACUUUCUAACAGAAUACUUUACAAAGCAGUUUCCAGCUUAGAUACUUCCUCCUACAGGGAACCUUCCCAAGGUGUUUCCUUGGCAGUGCUCCCUUCCUUAUCCCGCCACUGUCCCACAUGUCCCACCUAGGCCUUGAAGGGCAGAACCUGUGCUCUGUUCACUGUUGUAUUCCAGUGCCUGACACAACUAUUUGCACAGUAUUUAGGUGCUGAACAAAUAUUUAUUGAAUGCCAAAAUUGGUUCAUUUACUAAGCAGAAAGAAAGGAAAAUAUUUUUUGUUGGCAGUGUCUGCAAAGAGAUUUGUCUUUUCCCAUGAAAAUUGAGAAGUGGGGACAGAAAAGCAAGAAAGUGGGAGCAAAAGUAAUUGAGAUCCACAGUGGCUCAGGAGUGUUGACCGGUGCAGGGUGUGGUAGAAGCCCGUUAAUGGGUAGGGGAGCCAGAUACGGAGGCUCAGCUGGGCUGGGGGCAGGUCUGCAAGAAAUGGGGGGGUGUGGAGAAGGUUACCAGCCGUUACCAGAGUUUUCCUCUGCAUUGGGAAUUUCUAAGGUGUGUUUUUGUUUUUAAAACAAUAUCUGUACUUUCAAAAAUAUGGUUUCUUUGCUGCAAGGGGAACACAUUUAUUUUGUGAAAGUAAGUGUACCUAGUUAACAGUUUCCAUUUAUUAAUUUCUGGAAUAGUGUUUUGGUUACUUGGAAUGUGUGUGUGUAUUUUCUUUCUUUCUUUCUUUUUGAGACAGAGUCUCGCUCUGUCACCCAGGCUGGAGUGCAGUGGCGCCAUCUCGGCUUACUGUAGCCUCUGCCUCCCAGGUUCAAGCGAUUCUCCCGCCUCAGCCUCCCAAAGUACUGGGAUUACAGGUGUGAGCCACUGCGCCCGGCCUAUUUUCUUUCUAUUACAAGUCCCUUGCGGGAAAGAUGGUCGUAGCUCCUAUUCUAAAUGAACAGAAGUUCUGUCUUAGAAAUUUUCCCAUUUUACAAGUGUUCAAAGAGGACCAAAUUUCAUCCUCUUUCCCUGCCUGUGUCCUGGAAUCAGCUGAGAAGAAAGACAGGAGUAAGGUGGUCUUCAAUUCAGCCAGUCUUCAAUUGUUGGAGACCAAAAUUUACCUUUAUGCUGAUCAGGGUUAGAGCUGCUAUGCAGAACAUGGCUUAUCUCUGCGGGCAAGUGGCCUUCCUGAGGCUCAUCUCCAGAGCUGUGCAGCAGAAUGUUGCCCUCAAAAGAGGACAGAGGGCAGGACUGGCUAUGCAUGCAUGCUCACUCCCUUCUUCCAGAUUCACUGAGCCUGUUUUCCUUCUGAAUUAAGAGGUAAGAAAGUAACACCUGGAAAGAUGUACUUUCCCAAGGUCACGCAGAUAGCUGGCAACAGGUUUUUCUCCUGGGCUCUAGAGGCCUUUGGUCUGAGUAGAAAGGGCAUGGUUAUGGGGUUGGCCAGGCCUUGUGUUCACCACAUUCUGCUUCUGUGCUCUUAGCUUUCAUUUCUGCAUCUAUACCAUGGGGUUAAAAUUUCUACCCUCGGGAUUCCUGGGAGGGUUACCUAAGGUGUAACUGUUGAAUGACCUGAACCAGUGCUUUGCACUCAGAAUCAGCAAUGUAAAUAUCACUCAGCCAGCCUGGGGCACUUUCCUCUAUCAAACCUUACCAAUCCUUUUCUUCUUCUUCUUCUUUUUUUUUUUUUCUCUUCAAUUGAAACAGGGUCUCACUGUCUUGCCCAGGCUGAGGUGGAAUGUGGCACAAUCUCCGUUCACUGUAGCUUCCACUUCACAGGCUCAAUCAAUUCUCCAGCCUUAGCCUCCAAGUAGCUAUAGGCACGUGCCAUCACACCUGGCUAGUUUUUGUAUUUUUUGUAGAGAUGGGUUUUCACCAUGUUGCCUAGGCUGGUCUCAAACUCCUGAGCUCAAAGCGAUCUGCCUGACUUAGGCUUCGAAAAUGCUGGGAUUACAGGUGUGAGCCACCAUGUCCAGCCUCGUUGUUCUUUCUUUUAAUCACCCUGGCUUGGCACCUCAGAAAACAUGGUGAUUGGAGUUUAGCUUUCAGCAGGGUGGGACUUGGAUGUUGACUGUUUUAAUUUUGAUUUUUUUUUUUUUUUUUUUGAAACGGAGUCUCACUCUGUCGCCCAGGCUGGAGUGCAGUGGCGCGAUCUCGGCUCACUGCAAGCUCUGCCUUCCGGGUUCACGCCAUUCUCCUGCCUCAGCGUUGUGAGUAGCUGGGACUACAGGCGCCUGCCACCGCACCCAGCUAAUUUUUUGUAUUUUUAGUAGAGAUGGGGUUUCACCGUGGUCUCGAUCUCCUGACCUCGUGAUCUGCCCGCCUCGGCCUCCCAAAGUGCUGGGAUUACAGGUGUGAGCUACCGCACCCAGCCCAAUUUUGAUUUUUUAGGAGGAAAAAAAAUUGUUCCUAAGGAAGUCAAGUCCUAAAUUGAAAGACUUUCAUAUAUUACACAAACCCUAGAAAAACUUGGGUUACACCUGGGAUUGAUUUUGAAGUAGGGCGUUGAACUAUGUGUCCUGUUUAACCUCGAGGAGCAAAUGGCUUUCCAUUCUAAACAUUCUCAUUUCUUCUCUGGGACAUUCUUUAGGUGCUUGUUUGAGUUUCUGUUUUGUUAGGCACAUUAGAGGACUCUAUAUGAACAAGUUCCUAGGGGAGGAAAUUGGUGACUUAGAUGAAAGGGUGAAAAAGGUGAAACCUUCACAUUAUUGUGUAAGGGAUUGUCCCAGAAUGUGUGAAAUUUGAUGUAGUCCUUCUUGGCUUCGUUUUUUCCUCAGAUGUUCUGGAUGAAACAGUUCCCCCUGUCACACGUGGAGAUAAGGAUGUGGCUCUAGGCAGGGCAUAUCCUGUGUUUAAGACUGUGUUGACUCUUCUUUUACAGUGUCUGCCACUUGUUUCCUGCCUAGGUCUUUAGUUUUGAGUGAAGUACAGCUGUGAAGUCCUAGACUUGUAAUGCUAAGGCGUUCAUUAUGUUAAAUUCAGUUUCUCUUUUUCUUUUCUCUGCUUCACAUCAGCCUUGUACUUUAGCACGUUUCCAGUCCAGCCUUGGUAGCUGGGCUGCUGUUCUCCUUGACCCGUCCCUUUGCAAGCAGCAGACCACGGCCAGGGUUGGGAGUCCGGCUGGGCCACUGACCGCAGUGCUGAGGAAAGGUGGAGCGGGAGGCCCUUUCCUCCCAGCCUCGGGCUUCCUGUGCAAGCCACUGAGGAGGAAAAGGAGCUGGAGGGUGUGUGAACCCUCAGGUUAUACAAGCAGCACUUCUAUGCAACAAAGAAAAUGUAAAUUGCUGUAAAUUACCAAAAAAAAAAAAAAAAAAAAAAUUGCUGGCAAUCUGCUUUCCAGGGCAGAUGGAGGGUAGCUUUUAUUUAUACAUUGGUCAGCUGAUUGAGUAAUGUUUAAAAACCACCUUUACUUCUGGCACUUCUUGGCAGUAUCAGUUUUUUUUUUUUAAUGGAUAGAGAAGCUUUUUUAUUUUACAGAUAAUAACUGCAUAUCUUUACCUGAGGGAGCUCAGGUUCGCUCUAUCUAGCAGCUUCCACGUGUCAUCUCUGUAUGUGCAGUUGGUGCCUGCAUUAAGGAGGACGGACAGCCUUGUGGCGUUGGUGCCUCUGUUUUGUGUCUAAAGCUAUUUAUUUGGGGGUGGCUGCCCCAGGAGCAGCACAUCAAAGUGGUGUUCAGUUAUGCUGGCCAAGUGCUGAAUUGCAUUGUGUUUAUUUUUAUUUCCAAGGUUAUUUUAUUUUUUACACAUGAAAGCCUUUUUCCCUCCUAGAUUUUACUGUUUUUUUUUUUUUCCUGAUUAACAAAGAUGUACAGACUGAGGAGAAGUUUUUGAAAAUUUUGUAAAAAUGUUGAAAUUUUUAUGCAGAAAGAGAAACAAAGUGGGGGCCCAUCCCAAAUCUCACCAAUCAGGCAGAAACUAUUUGUCAUACUGGAUACGGUUUCUCUCUCUCUCUUUUUUUUUUUUUUUUUGUGGGGGGGAUCUUUUCAUUAAAAAACUCUUCUGUAGGUAUCUUAACAGCACUUGCAUGGUCCUUAGGAGAUGAAGGUGUUUCGCCAUUUCUGGAGUGCUGCACAUGUAGUUUUCUUCUUUUUAAAUUGUCAGUGGCCCUGGCCAGAUUACUAAUUCCCUACUAAGUUGCCAGUUGUGCUAGUACCCCACCCUCCAAAAUCCAUAUUGACCUUCUGUAUCAAAAUGGCUAAGUCGUCAGAAACCAGCAGUGGGCAAACGUUAGGGUCUCAGCUUUCCUCCUUUCUUUCACUUGCUUGGCUUCAUUGGCUUUGAAUCGGAUAGACCCGGGUAGGAACCUCACCUAGCCCCUCCACUAACUUUGUGUCCUCCGGCAAAAUAAAUCUCCCUAAGCCUCUAUUUCCUAUAUGCAAAAUAGGGAUGAUAGUAUUACCCAAUUCCAGGGUUAUUGUAAGAAUUCAGAGGCAAGUUGUGAAGGGUGUGGCAUGGUGUCUGGAAUGGGUGAUGAUACAGUUCCCUAAGGGGAGCUGCUGCCACCUCUGUGCUGGGGACUCUCCCUUUGCCCCAUCCCAAGAAUUUGGGUUGGCUAAUCCUGCCCUGUCUGGUUUUGGAUGAGGGACCAGGAAAGAAAGGGAGGCAGGAUAGGGGAGGUGUUUUUGAGAAAAACCUUCUUUUUCCCUCUGCAAGUAUUUGUUUCAGGCAGUACGUGAACCCUCGAAGACUGAUCGGGGCUGGUCCUGGGUCACCCCAGCAGGGUUCAGUGAAGUGGGCCAGGGGCACUGGACCCUCGGCUUUCUCCCUGCAGGGGGAUCUGCCUCCCUGGCCUCGCCUCUUGUGAUCUUCUAUGCAUGUUCACUCCUUACUCACUCUGAGCCUUCUGACUCUGACCAGCCUGUGUUCCUGGCAUUCUUUUGAUGAUGUAAGUGUUUCACACCCUAUCUGCAACCAAGCAGGAGGACGGAGAGGACUUCUGCAGCAAAGAGUACCUCUAGAAAUUGCUUUUGUGAGGUUCUUUGAGGUGCUAAUCACCUAACUUUUAUUUGAAUUGCUCUGACUUAUCAUUUAAUAACUCCGGAGGACUUUUUACUUCCUUGGCAGGAGGAGGAAGGUGAUUCCUCAGAUAAAACCAAAACCUAGAGCUGCACUUCUGAAGGAAAUUGCUGCUCAGGUAGGGCUGGAUGUGUAGGUGUUCUCCAUGGGCCCAUGCCGUGCCUGUACCAGCGUCCUGAAUUGACGGCAGCAGAGGGGUAUCUUUCUUCAUUCUUCAUUAUUUAUUGCCUGAGGCAGAAUGAAUACUUGUACACUUGGGAUUUCAGCCAUGCCUUUUAAGGGCUGUGAACAGACUUAUCAAAGAGCCAUCUUGAGUGGCCUGUAGGGCGGAAGGGAGAAUACAGGACAAGAAAGUGGAUGGAAUUAAUGGGAACAAGAGUGACAUAAAAUAGUUUAACCCCCUGUGGCCCUCUUCAGACUUUUACAUUUGUCUAUUUUUAUUUAUUUAAAAUUUUUUAACUUUUGUGGGUACGUAGGUGUAUAUAUUUAUGGGGUACAUAAGAUUUUUUGAUACAGGCAUAUAAUAAUCAUAUCAGAGUAAUAUCACCCCAAGCAUUUAUCAUUUGUAUUACAAACAAUCCAUAUAUAUUCUUUUAGUUAUUUUAUUUUGUUAUCUUAUUUAUUUAUUUAUUUUGAGACGGAGUCUUGCUCUGUCACCCGGGCUGGAGUGCAGUGGCACAAUCUCAGCUCACUGGAACCCCCGCCUCCUGAGUUCAAGCGAUUCUCCUGCCUCAGCCUCCUGUGUAGCUGGGAUUACAGGCCGGUGCCACCAUGCCCAGCUAAUUAUUGUAUUUUUAGUAGAAAUGGGGUUUCACCAUGUUGGCCAGGCUGAUCUUGAACUCCUAACCUCAGAUGUUCCACCCACCUCGGCCUCCCAAAGUGCUGGGAUUACAGGUGUGAGCUAUCGCACCCAGCCUAUUAUUUAUUUUUGAGAGAUAGGAUCUUGCUCUGUUGCCCAGGCUGAGUCAUGCUCACUGUAUACUCUACCUUCUGGGCUCAGGCAAUCCUCCCACCUCAGCUUCCCAAGUAGCUGGAACCACAGGUGCACAGCCGCCACUCCUGGCUAAUAUUUUUAUUUUUUGUUCAGACGGUGGGGAGGCUCUUGCUGUGUUGCCCAAGCUGAUCCUGAACUCCUGGGCUCAAGCGAUCCUCCUCCCUCCGCCUUCCAAAGUGCUGAGAUUACAGGUAUGAACCACUAUGGCUAGCCUGGUCUACAGAAAUGUCUAAUUUUCUUCAGACUUUGUUCUCCCUUCAAAUUAGGUUUCAUCUGGCAGAGUGGCUACUCCAUUUGUUUGCAAGCCUCUGCCCUUGAUGUUCAGAUUCCUGCUGCUGGUGGAGCCGGCUGAGUUUCCCAGAUGGGCUCCACCUGCCUCCUCCUCGGUUGCUGCAGCAUUCAUUGCUUCGUGCUUCCUGUCUGGCUCGCCUCCAAAUGAGCCUGUUCAUUUCCUUUCUCCGGAAACUGUCCUUAUCACUGAGGUUCAAAAGUUCCAUAAAGGAUAUGGCAGUCUUGAGACUUGACCUCCAAACUUUGACCUUAAUAAAAACUGGUUUUUUAAACCCAGCCAACCUGAAUGAGUGGACUAUGGCUUUUGAUUGCUGUUAGCUGAAGGAGAUGUAUGGCUGCUGGGUGACGCCUUGAACAGUGAGAUGUUAUAUAUAAUCUUGAAUUUGGGGUGGUGCUUGUGUCACCACUCGGAAUUAUGUUGUCAGUCUCACUUCCCUCCUGGCUUCUUGGCAAUCGUCUUUAUUAAUGUUUUCAAUUUUCUUACUAUCCAGUGAACUUACUUUGUAUUUAUUGUUUGGGGUAGUGUUGUAGAUGGUAUUACUAUUUGAAAACUUACUGUUGAAAGGGACCGUAGUCCAGUGGCCUCUUUUAAUAAUCAGGGAAAACUGAGUCCAUGAAGACACGCCUGCCUUUGAAAACCUAAGAAUCCACUGCUUUUUCUGUUGAGACAGACCCCACAGAGAUCUCCGAGAGGACGGCUGCAGCAAGAGUGCUGACUCCCAUGCAGCCGCAUUCCUUUUCUAAUUGUCAAAGCUGAUUAGUGGAUUUGGAUGUGCGUGGCUCGGAGUCCUCUAAUAAUCUUUCCUUUCUUACAUAGCUCACCUAGAAUUUGAGGAAAAUUAAACCAGUUGUGAAAUAUAUCACGUUUCAGAAAUGAACGGCAUCUUAAUUGAUUCCCUUUGAGAACACAUCAGACUGGGAUUUCUGAGUGUAAUCUGGUAUGCCUUGAGGUGGGGACCUCAUGCUGGGGCACUCAGAGGAGACUGGUCCACCUCCAAGUUUGUUUUCUGGCUCCAAACAAAUGAGUGGCUGUUUGACUGUUGGCACACUACCCAGUUUUAAAAGUACAACCAUAUAGGGUAUGGAGGGCUGGUAACCAGGGGGUUUAAAAAGUGAGGUCAUGGAAGGCCCAGAUGAAGCUCUUUUAAUGUGUAUCACAACUGCAAUUAAUCUUAUUAACAUGCUGGGCCUGUUCCUGCUUUCGCUGCCCCAGGUGUGUGAGAGUAUUUAGGGGGCAUGCUUUGAAGGAUUCUUGUUCUUUGAUGAUGCACAUGGAUAACAGAAGUACAUCAAACUUUGUAUCUGGCAUUAAAAGGGCUUUUGUUUGCCUCUGUAGAUUCAUUCAGUUUUGAGAAGAGAGCAAAAAGCUUCAUGCCAAUUGAUAAGAUGUACAAAAGAGGGUGGAUUGCAAAUGCAGUCUUGCAGCAGUGAGCUCUAUGACCAGAUCAGAAUCAGCUGAACAGGAAUGGAGCCCUCUUCUAUAUCCAACACUAAGGAUGUUGAGAAAGAGAAGGAAACCCACAGUUACCUCAGCAAAGAGGAGAUCAAAGAGAAAGUUCAUAAAUACAACUUAGCAGUCACAGACAAGUUGAAGAUGACCUUGAAUUCAAAUGGGAUUUACACUGGCUUCAUUAAAGUACAGAUGGAACUCUGCAAACCUCCACAGACUUCUCCAAAUUCUGGAAAACUCUCUCCCAGUAGCAAUGGCUGUAUGAAUACACUUCAUAUCAGCAGCACAAACACUGUCGGGGAAGUGAUCGAGGCCCUGCUCAAAAAGUUUCUCGUGACUGAGAGCCCUGCCAAGUUUGCACUUUAUAAGCGUUGUCACAGGGAAGACCAAGUCUACGCCUGCAAGCUCUCAGACCGGGAACAUCCACUCUACCUGCGUUUGGUAGCAGGGCCCAGAACAGACACACUUAGUUUUGUUCUUCGUGAACAUGAAAUUGGAGAGUGGGAAGCCUUCAGCCUUCCAGAACUACAGAAUUUCUUGCGCAUCUUGGACAAGGAAGAAGAUGAACAGCUGCAGAACCUGAAGAGGCGCUACACAGCCUACAGGCAGAAGCUGGAAGAAGCCCUCCGUGAGGUGUGGAAGCCUGAUUAAAGCGGGGCUCCCUGCCCGUGAGGCCCGGUGCAGGACCGAUGUACAAAACAGCAGCAAGUGCCUCUCUUCUCAGAGGGCUGCUGUCUUGCCCCACUAUGCUAGGGUCUUCGCCUUUCUAUCUGUAGAUUUUGUUCCCCAAACCUGGUCACACAGCAUCCUGCACCUUAGCGUCCCAUGUAAGGGACUCUGCAAGCUUGUUGUUCAGCACCGCAGUGUUACCUCUUGGCAAGCUGUGAACCUGUCGCCUCAUCAGGAGCAUUCGAGGGUGCUUGGAAGCAUGAACUCUGGGGGUGUUUUUUUUUUUGGUUAUUUUAAUUAUGUGAUGAUGCUGUUAAGCUUACAGAUAUGCAGUUGAUUUUUUAAAAAGCUUAACUAGGAAUCUUUCUGAAUACUUGUCCUAUUUUGAAACUACCUGUCUGGUUUUUUGUUUGGUUUUGUUUUCUUUUUUUAAUGUCAGAGGAAUCUAUCCAUGUGAAUCGAAAGGCACAGGAAUCUAGGAACUCUGAGGAAUUUAUUGUGAAGGAUUUUGUUAGGGGGUUGACAGAGAAAGCAAAGUGUAAGUUUGGAAGAAGGCAUGUGCGGUGGUGGCGAGUGCUGCGGGCUAUGGAAGGUGACUUGGCUUUUCAGUUAGGGGUAGUGGAGAAAGGGGUAGUUGCUUGUAAACGAGUUAAAAGCAUUCAGUGUGGAGGUGUUAAACCCAUUUUAGGAUCGCUUGGUUUCCUGGUGGGUAGAAUAUGGGAACAGAGCCAGAGGCAGGAGCUAAACCAAAAGGAGGGACCCAUGAACUCUGCAGCUGACCAAUCAGAGAAUCAGGCAGGUGUAGCCUACUGACCUGGGCAGAGGUGGGCCUCACGCAGCUGGAUCCGACCCUUUAAUUCUGCCCUUUUGGAGUGGAAGGUCUGAUUGGUGUAGCUGCUCUGCAUAGGCAGGACAGUGACAGUUCACUAACUCUUGUUAAGUUACAUAGUGUAUAGCUUUCCCCCCACAGGUGGUUUUCAAAGUUGAGACGGAAUUUGGGUAGGGGCAGCUGUUUUUCCCUUGAUUGUUAGCUAGGAUAUUUGUCAAGUAAACUUUGGUGACAAUCACUCUCUUCCCUUUUAUUCCUCCUUUCCUUUUCCUUUCUUCCCUUUUUUCUUUCCUUCCCUGCUGUCUCCCACCCUACCUUGUUCUUUUCCUCCCUCCCUCCCUCCCUCCCUCCCUCCCUCCCUCCUUCCCUCCCUCUCUCUCCCUCUCCCUUUCUUUUCUACAUUGAAAUCUGUUCUUACAUAAUAGAGAACAGGGCUAUUGAAUAAAGACCCAAUCCUACCAGAUCUUUAGUUCUAAAGGGCAACUUGACUGUGAGUAGGAGGGCCCCCAAGAAAGGGAGGAAAGUCCACACCCAGCUAACCACACAACAGGGCUUCAUUAUGGAAAUAUUUUAACAAAAGUACAUGUUAUUACCAACCAAAGAGAUGCAUGUGCAAUAGAAGCCUUCCUUAAAAACAGGCUAAAUAACCUCAUUUUAUGCAGCAGUUUAAUCUGAGAACAGAGGGAAAGGUGUGCAGUGGUUCCAGAGGGGCCUUAUAUUCUAUUUUUAGUCUAGAUAUUUUUUGUUUAUAAAUUCCCAAGGAAUUGUUAACACUUUGGUGACACCUAAUGGAUUCUUUUUGAAAUUCCAAGGUGCUUCAGUUCUUUGCCCAAGUGAACUGUGCCUUUUAUUGCAUUUCUGUUCGUCUCUUGGUGGCUCUUCUGACUUUUUGGAGAAUACCCAUCUUGUUGGAGGCAGACUUAAGUUGUUAUGCUGUGCCACACAAUUUACUGAGACAAUCAUAUCUUCCUAAGCAUUUAAGGAAAGUUGAAAAAAAUAGAAUUAGCUAUAAAAUAUGUAUGGCACAUCUUGUUUAAUUUUGCAUGUAACUUCUCUUUUGUACAUUGAUGAGGUUUUAGUGACAUUGUCAUCCAACACUUUACCUUUAUUGUUCAGGGAAUGCCUUCGUGAUUUUUUGUACUGGUUUUAUUAUUCAGACUAUGGCCUGGAUUUGAGUAUAUUGUUAUUACCACCUGGUUUUUUAAUUAUUCAUCCCAGUAAACUUAUAUUUUGUGAAGCAUUUGUUUCUCAGAUUAAGACACUGUUAGAACCUAAAGUAGUAGCUGAUGGGUAUCUGUGAAUUUUUUUUUUUUUUUUUUUUUUACUUGAAGUAGAUUGUCUGAAUAGGCAUCCUCAUCUAUAUUUACCCAAAACCUCGCUUACUGUCAUGUGCACUACAAAUUGCAAUUUGGAAACCUACUGUAUUGAAAUUCUGUCAGUUUAUGGUUCUUGAAGACUGAUGUCCUUUCCCAAACACUGGUUACUGCAGCAGCAUUUUUAAUGUGUAAGUGAAGAAAAAAGGCCACUAAGGCCAAAGAUUUUUUAAGAAUCAUUGUACAAAUCAUUAUGUUAAACUAUCUAAGCUUUGCUGUAAUACUGUUUUCUCUUCAAUAUGUGAUGGUACAGGAAGGAUGUUAAAUGAAGGGGUGGUAUUGCAGGAGAGCAUUUUAAAUGGCAGAAGUAAAAAGUUAUAAUAUUUAUAAUUUUGAUGGGUUUAAGUUUAUUUUUGUAGGGAAGAUUUUUCUCCCCUAAAAUAGUUUCUAGAAUGGCAAAAUUGUUUCCAUUAUUAAAAAUUGAAGUUAUUA